CGAGGACGCCCGAACGCCGAACUUCCUGUGCUCGGGAGGGGGCAGGGUUUUGUACUGUGGGAGUCUGAGAGCGAGGAGGUCCGAAAGCCGAAUCACAGUCGUUCGGAAAGAGGAGGAGCGAAGGCUCGAGCGUCCGGAAGAGGGUGUGGCCUCGGCGGUGCCUUAGCCUCCAGAGCUUCUGACCGCUGACGGGAACACCCGAAGGGGGACGCCCACUUUGCAAGAGGGUGGUGCCAAAAUGGACCUUUGUAAGGGGGCGUGUCGCCGCGCUUGCGGAGGUUUGUUUUUCACGCUCCAAGGCGCAAUGGAGGAUGCUGGUGGUGGAGGUGGCGAACGGCCGCUCCCUGGUGUGGGGAGCCGAGGCGGUGCAGGCCCUCCGGGAGCGCCUGGGUGUGGGGGGCCGCACGGUAGGCGCCCUGCCCCGCGGGCCCCGCCAGAACUCGCGCCUGGGCCUCCCGCUGCUGCUGAUGCCCGAAGAGGCGCGGCUCUUGGCCGAGAUCGGCGCCGUGACUCUGGUCAGCGCCCCGCGUCCAGACUCUCGGCACCACAGCCUGGCCCUGACAUCCUUCAAGCGCCAGCAAGAGGAGAGCUUCCAGGAGCAGAGCGCCUUGGCAGCUGAGGCCCGGGAGACCCGUCGUCAGGAGCUCCUGGAGAAGAUUACGGAGGGCCAGGCUGCUAAGAAGCAGAAACUAGAACAGGCUUCAGGGGCCAGCUCAAGCCAGGAGGCCGGCUCGAGCCAGGCUGCCAAAGAGGAUGAGACCAGUGAUGGCCAGGCUUCGGGAGAGCAGGAGGAAGCUGGCCCCUCGUCUUCCCAAGCAGGACCCUCAAAUGGGGUAGCCCCCUUGCCCAGAUCUGCUCUCCUUGUCCAGCUGGCCACUGCCAGGCCUCGACCGGUCAAGGCCAGGCCCCUGGACUGGCGUGUCCAGUCUAAAGACUGGCCCCACGCCGGCCGCCCUGCCCACGAGCUGCGCUACAGUAUCUACAGAGACCUGUGGGAGCGAGGCUUCUUCCUCAGUGCGGCUGGCAAGUUCGGAGGUGACUUCCUGGUCUAUCCUGGUGACCCCCUCCGCUUCCACGCCCAUUAUAUCGCUCAGUGCUGGGCCCCCGAGGACACCAUCCCACUCCAAGACCUGGUUGCUGCUGGGCGCCUUGGAACCAGCGUCAGAAAGACCCUGCUCCUCUGUUCUCCGCAGCCUGAUGGUAAGGUGGUCUACACCUCCCUGCAAUGGGCCAGCCUGCAGUGAACUCCAGAGACCUAGGGGAUGUGGCUGUGUCGGCAGCAAGAGCCUUUCUGGAUGUUCCCCAGCUCUUCUCUGGGAGUCUAGAACAUCCUCCUACCUUUCUCCGCGGUUAGUUUUUGAUUCCAGGUUUUCGAACACUACAUCUUUUUUAUGUUCUUCCUUGUUUCAAAGCACUUAUUGGCUGUGUUUUUGUAGUUACCUAUUUUCACACUGUGAGCUUCCCGAGAAUGGGGCCUGGGUUUGAUUCAUCUGUUUUCUACAGGGUUUAAGUCUCAGGAGGUCUCAAUAAACUUGGUAUAUAAAUGUUCAUGAUUUGAAUGUUUGCGACAGUCCUGGAACCCGUGGAUGGUCUCAUCUGCAUGUACAGGUGAGAAAAAGGCCUGGAGGGGGGGGACUGACUUGCCCAAAGUCACACACUUAGUAAAUAGCAGGCCUGGCCUUUCAAAAUUGGUUUUUCUGACUCCUAAAUCUGCACUCUUUCUACCUCACUAAACUUCCUCUUGAAAAGAUUUCUAUGAAAUUUCCCAGAUGCAUACAAACGUUAUAAAUAAAAAUAUAGGCUGGGCACGAUGACCCACACCUGUAAUCCCACAGAACUUUUGGAGGCCAAGGCAGGGGGAUCGCUUGAGCCCAGGAGUUUGAGACCAGCUCUGGCAACAUUGUAAUACCCAGUCUCUACAAAAAAUAAUUUAAAAAAAAAUUAGCCAGGGAUCCCUUGAGCCUGGGAAGUUGAGGCUGCUGUGAGCUGUGAUUGCACCACUGCCCUCCAGCCUGGGAGACAGAGCAAGAACCUGUCUCAAAAAAUAUAUAUAUGUGUGUGUGUAUAUAUGUAAAUAUACACACAUGUAUGUAUAUAUAUGUGUGUGUAUAUAUAUAUAUAUUAUGAAAGGAAAUGAGUAUUGUAAUUUUAGGAGUUCAGAGCCUGGGGAGAAAGGAAGGACUCUGGAAGGCGUUCUGCUUUUUCAUGGCCUGGGUAGUGGUGGAGAAUUUUUUUGAUACUGUAUAUUUAUAUUUUAGACUCUUUUUUGGAUGUGUUAUAUUCUGCAAUUUUUAUAAAAGCUAAAACACAUGUAUUUGUAAAAAAUUUGCACUUAUGAAAUCAUUUACCCAUGUUUUUGCUUAAGAAAGUACUAGAACACUACCACUAUUCCAAUAAUUACACCUUUAUCUUAUCAA